GCCCUGGACACCCCCUUUCUCCCAGCCCCGAGGUCCUCCUACAGCGGCCCAGCCCGCUGGCCCCUGACGGACCCACGCAUUUCUGAUUCCCAUUCCUCCCCCAUUCCCUCUUCCCCGAAGCGCAGACCGCCUGCGCCCCACCUCUACCUGGACCUCUGGUCCCCUCUCUCUGGUCCCAGCCCCUCCGUCCCUACAAAAAUGCCAGGCGCCCCUGGUCCCUAGGCCACCCGCGCCCAUCCCCACUCUCCACUCUGGAGCCACUCCACCCGACCCCCUGCAGGCCUCGGCCUUCUCCCCAGCAGCCCCGGCCCAAGCCCGCCCUAUUCCUGGACCCUGAGAUACUCCCAGCGCCCCUGAUUGUCCCAGUUCAUAACCAAAGUGGACUGGAACUGGCCCACUCUCACGUCCACCUCCCCGCAAUUGCUGAGACACCUCUUCUUGAUCUGCUACAUUAAGGGUGGCGGGAGGAGGAUGUCCCAGAAAUGUCCAAGAGGCGCAGCUCGCAGAGGUUACGCCGGUGCCCGGGAGGCCUGGGUUCGCCUACCCACGUCGCCACACUAGGCUGAGCGCCCGUCGCUGCCUGGGACCCCCGCUUAGUGCCACCGAGAGCGCACAGGCCGCGCCCCGCUGCCGCUCCACGCCCCGCGUCCCAGAGGAGGGCGCGAACCCGAGGCCUGGCCCAGUGCCCUGGAGCAAAGUUCCCCGGAGUUGAGGGGCCAGUAUAAAUUAUCAACCGAAAACCCGUAGGGGAGAAAGGGGGAUCGGCCGGCCUUGAUCUUUUCUCUGUGCAAAUAUUCCUCUUCCUCCGCGGCGCCUCCUCCCCUUCUGAGAACCGCUGGCUACAGAUCGGCACCUGCCGCCCUGCGGGGGAGCAGGAGCUGGGGUGGGGACUGUGAGGGGAGUGUUGCCUGCCCCCAACCGCAGCCGCCCAGCUGCGACCCCAUUGGCUGGAGGCGGAGUAACCUUGGCCCACAAGCUCUGGCCCCUGGCCCAGGUCAUGUUGCAACCCGAUCGGCCAGGGCGUCGGACCCGUGUGGAAAGUUCAAAUUCCCGUCCCUUCUCCCUCCCUCCCCAAAUGUCACGCGACUGCCUGGGACAGGGCAUCUAAGGUCCUGGUACACCGGAUGCCGGCACUCCUCCUCCUAAGGGUCUCCCAUUUCCCACCCAACCCCAACUUUGGCUGCUCAUUAUAUACUACACAUCACUCUAUUUGGGAGGGGGCCUCACUUCCAACCCUGACGAUGGGUGACCAAAGAGGAGAGGUUCUGGGGAGCUGGCAAGUGGCAAGCUGGUGUCUCCCAAGUGGAAGAAUUUCAAAGGCCUCAAGCUGCUCUGCAGAGACAAGAUCCGCCUGAACAACGCCAUCUGGAGGGCCUGGUAUAUCCAGUAUGUGAAGCGGAGGAAGAGCCCCGUGUGUGGCUUCGUGACCCCCCUGCAGGGGCCUGAGGCUGAUGCGCACCGGAAGCCGGAGGCCGUGGUCCUGGAGGGGAACUACUGGAAGCGGCGCAUCGAGGUGGUGAUGCGGGAAUACCACAAGUGGCGCAUCUACUACAAGAAGCGGGUCAGUGGGGGAGGGCCAGGGAGGCCCCAGAGCUUUCCUCCUGCGGCUGCCGGCUACCGCCCGCCUCGGAAGAUCCCUGGAAAGGGGAUCCUGACCCCCGAGCUUGCGCCCCUCGGGCCCUCCAUUCAGUCCCGGGCCGACAGCGCCACCGUGUGGCCACAGCGUCUCCUAGCGGCCUCCUUACCUAGGGGUCGGCUCCGUAAGCCCAGCAGGGAAGAUGACCUCCUGGCCCCUAAGCAGGCGGAAGGCAGGUGGCCGCCGCCGGAGCAAUGGUGCAAACAGCUCUUCUCCAGUGUGGUCCCCGUGCUGCUGGGGGACCCAGAGGAGGAGCCGGGUGGGCGGCAGCUCCUGGACCUCAAUUGCUUUUUGUCCGACAUCUCAGACACUCUCUUCACCAUGACUCAGUCCGGCCCUUCGCCCCUGCAGCUGCCGCCUGAGGAUGCCUACGUCGGCAAUGCUGACAUGAUCCAGCCGGACCUGACGCCACUGCAGCCAAGCCUGGAUGACUUCAUGGACAUCUCAGAUUUCUUUACCAACUCCCGCCUCCCACAGCCGCCCAUGCCUUCAAACUUCCCAGAGCCCCCCAGCUUCAGCCCCGUGGUUGACUCCCUCUUCAGCAGUGGGACCCUGGGCCCAGAGGUGCCCCCGGCUUCCUCGGCCAUGACCCACCUCUCUGGACACAGCCGUCUGCAGGCUCGGAACAGCUGCCCUGGCCCCUUGGACUCCAGCGCCUUCCUGAGUUCUGAUUUCCUCCUUCCUGAAGACCCCAAGCCCCGGCUCCCACCCCCUCCUGUACCCCCACCUCUGCUGCAUUACCCUCCCCCUGCCAAGGUGCCAGGCCUGGAGCCCUGCCCCCCACCUCCCUUCCCUCCCAUGGCACCACCCACUGCUUUGCUGCAGGAAGAGCCUCUCUUCUCUCCCAGGUUUCCCUUCCCCACCGUCCCUCCUGCCCCAGGAGUGUCUCCGCUGCCUGCUCCUGCAGCCUUCCCACCCACCCCACAGUCUGUCCCCAGCCCAGCCCCCACCCCCUUCCCCAUAGAGCUUCUACCCUUGGGGUAUUCGGAGCCUGCCUUUGGGCCUUGCUUCUCCAUGCCCAGAGGCAAGCCCCCCGCCCCAUCCCCUAGGGGACAGAAAGCCAGCCCCCCUACCUUAGCCCCUGCCACUGCCAGUCCCCCCACCACUGCGGGGAGCAACAACCCCUGCCUCACACAGCUGCUCACAGCAGCUAAGCCGGAGCAAGCCCUGGAGCCACCACUUGUAUCCAGCACCCUCCUCCGGUCCCCAGGGUCCCCGCAGGAGACAGUCCCUGAAUUCCCCUGCACAUUCCUUCCCCCGACCCCGGCCCCUACACCGCCCCGGCCACCUCCAGGCCCGGCCACAUUGGCCCCUUCCAGGCCCCUGCUUGUCCCCAAAGCGGAGCGGCUCUCACCCCCAGCGCCCAGCGGCAGUGAACGGCGGCUGUCAGGGGACCUCAGCUCCAUGCCAGGCCCUGGGACUCUGAGCGUCCGUGUCUCUCCCCCGCAACCCAUCCUCAGCCGGGGCCGUCCAGACAGCAACAAGACCGAGAACCGGCGUAUCACACACAUCUCCGCGGAGCAGAAGCGGCGCUUCAACAUCAAGCUGGGGUUUGACACCCUUCAUGGGCUCGUGAGCACACUCAGUGCCCAGCCCAGCCUCAAGGUGAGCAAAGCUACCACGCUGCAGAAGACAGCUGAGUACAUCCUUAUGCUACAGCAGGAGCGUGCGGGCUUGCAGGAGGAGGCCCAGCAGCUGCGGGAUGAGAUUGAGGAGCUCAAUGCCGCCAUUAACCUGUGCCAGCAGCAGCUGCCCGCCACAGGGGUACCCAUCACACACCAGCGUUUUGACCAGAUGCGAGACAUGUUUGAUGACUACGUCCGAACCCGUACGCUGCACAACUGGAAGUUCUGGGUGUUCAGCAUCCUCAUCCGGCCUCUGUUUGAGUCCUUCAACGGGAUGGUGUCCACGGCAAGUGUGCACACCCUCCGCCAGACCUCACUGGCCUGGCUGGACCAGUACUGCUCUCUGCCCGCUCUCCGGCCAACUGUCCUGAACUCCCUACGCCAGCUGGGCACAUCUACCAGUAUCCUGACCGACCCGGGCCGCAUCCCUGAGCAAGCCACACGGGCAGUCACAGAGGGCACCCUUGGCAAACCUUUAUAGUCCUGGCCAGACCCUGCUGCUCACUCAGCUGCCCUGGGGGCUGCUUUCCCUGGGCACGGGCUCCAGGGAUCAUCUCUGGGCACUCCCUUCCUGCCCCAGGCCCUGGCUCUGCCCUUCCCUGGGGGGUGGAGCAGGGUCCAGGUUUCACACUUGCCACCUCCUGGAGGUCAAGAAGAGCAGAGUCCCCGUCCCUGCUCUGCCACUGUGCUCCAGCACCGUGACCUUGGGUGACUCGUCCGCUGUCUUUGGACCGCUGUGUUUCAAUCUGCAAAAUGGGGAUGGGGAAGGUUCAAUCAGCAGAUGACCCCCAGGCCUUGGCAGCUGUGACAUUGGGGGCCUAGGCUGGCAACUCCGGGGGCUCAACGGUGGAAAGAGGAGGAUGCUGUUUCUCUGUCACCUCCACUUGCUCCCCGACAGGUGGGGCACAGACCUCUGUUCCUGAGCAGAGAAGCAGAAAAGGAGGUUCCCUCUCUCUGCUCCUUCACUGCUGACCCAGAGGGGCUGCAGGAUGGUUUCCCCUGGGAGAGGCCAGGAGGGCCUGAUCCCAGGAGACACCAGGGCCAGAGUGACCACAGCAGGGCAGGCAUCAUGUGUGUGUGUGUGUGUGGAUGUGUGUGUGUGGGUUUUGUAAAGAAUUCUUGACCAAUAAAAGCAAAAACUGUC